UUCCUCCCUUUCUGAUCCUUUAUCCCACUUUCUUUUUCUUCCUCUUCCUUCUCCUUCUUGUCAAAGACAUAGAGGAUUGAGUUAUUAUCACUGAUCCAUACAAAGUCCCUCUCUCAUUUAUUUUCUUUCAUUCCCACCCCCCAUUUCUAUUCCUCGUCUUCGCAUGUGCAACCUUCCUAAUAUGUUUGAUAUGCAUCUUUUUGUUUGUAUGUAUUUUUAGAAAAUGUUAAAUAAAAAAAGAUUUAAAACAAGCCCUGCAAAGGCAGGAAAGCUGAACUGGCUGCUGAGCCCCUUCUGCUUGGCCACGCAGUACCCACGCCUGUAGCCCCUGGAAUCCUAGUGUGGGCUAAGGUGGAGUGGACCCUCUGGCUUGGUCACGGCGCAAUGGGCCACCUGGAAACCAUCCAAAAGAGACCUACCAGCCCGUGCCCUAGGUGCAGCUGCCACCUGCACGUCAGGCACCAGCAGCAAUGGCCAGACCAUCCCUGAUUCUCCAUGCCCUCCCCAUCCCCGCCCCAACAGCAAGGACUCCCUGACAGGACGCUGUGGUAGUGGCUGUCAGGAAGUCGGCUGGGCGGGUGCAUAAGGAUAAAGAUAGACUCUCAGCCCCAUCCCGAUGGCCACGACGUGCUCAUCCCCUGGCAGCUCCUCAGCCCUAUCCUAGUGGCCACAGAGUGGCAUGCAGGCAGCAGCCUUGGGAACCCCGAUUGCCCCUCCUCACACGUGCCCAUCACACGACUUGGGCGACGGGGAGGUGAAGUCAGGUUGUGGCCCCAGCGGCGCCAUGAGGAACGAGAACCUGCGCUCAGCCUCAUCCCUGUGGCUGCAGAGUGCCAAGCGCCAGGUCCUGCACUCUGGGCGCGGGUCAGGAGCAGCUGGCAAGGGCAGCGCAGCCUGUGGGGCCCUUGGGCGUGGCCGGCCGCAGCUCCGGGAAGCCAGGUCAGCCCAUGGGCGCUAGCCGCCACCAGCACAUGGAGCAGGGGUCGCCGAGGAUUGGGAAUCUCCGACCAGGCGGGCGCCUCCAGCCGCGCGGACCCCGGGGCCAGCCCGGCCGCGGCAAGUCAGGCAGUCUGCGGCAGGAGCGCCGGGCAUGGGCUUUGGCCCGGGGUGUAGGAGGCGCGCACCCUCUGGCCGGAUGGGCGGCGCACUCAGGGCCCAGGAGGCCAUCCCAGGGGAGCCCCGCCAGCCCCCGCCGGAGCCCGAGCUGCAGCUGCCACCUGCAAGUGGUGCGCUGGCUGCAGCAGUGGCAACCCCGGAUCCCGUCCUCCCGCCUCACACCCAUCAGCACGGACCCCGGGGGCGACGCAGUGGCGAAGUCGGGCUGUGGGCCCACGGGCGGCACCAGGCGGAGAAGCACCACUCAACCCCAUCCCUGGGCUGCAGAGGGCCCAGCGCGGGGGCCCGGAGCAUCGGGAGCCGGUGGAAGAGGAGAAGAGCGCGCAGGCCACAGUCAAACAGGCCCUGGGGCAGGGCGCGCCUUGCGCUCCAGGGAGCCCCGCCAGCCGGCGGCACCUGAGCAGCAACCGCGGCCUGCACUGGGCGCCGCGAGAGAGCUGCUAGGGCGGUUUCUCCGCCUAGGGCCUGUUGGGCGGGGCCGGCUAAGGUGCACGUGCUCGCUGGUCCUAACCGUUCUGUUGGGCGUUUCUGCUGAGAGGCGGGAGGCGCUGAGAGUAUGUGCAAAGGUCCGUGGACGGACCGCAUUGCUUGUUGUUGCGCUUCGGAGGCGGAGAUCCCCGAAGGCGAGCUGAAAUACGGCUGGAGAGUUCCCAGGAUACAAUUUGCAGCAGACGAGUAUGGAAGACUACCAGCCGGAGUGGUGGCCCACCCUCAGGGAGCGCUUGUGCUCCGACGGCUUCUCAUUUCCCCAAUACCACAUUAAAUCAUCUCAUCUGAGGAGGAUCCACAGAGCUGUCUUCUGUGGUAAUCUGGAGAAACUGAACUACCUUCUGUUCACGUUAUCAUGACGCUGCCUGAGUAGUUGUCGACCUUGUUUUCACAUUAACUGGCUGUUUUGUUGUGGCUGCACUUCUGUUUCAUUACCUUCAUCAGAAUCAUAGCUUGGAGGCUUCAUAGCUCCCUGAUUCAAUUCUGUCCCAUAUUUCAACUUGUGGUAUUUGGCUCUUUUCUGUUUAAGAGCAUACUCCAACAUUCUGAUCAUCCUCACGAGAUCCUUCUUCAAAUUUUCUUGGCCCUUCCUUUCUCCCUGUAGGAAGGCAAUCUGGGCCGUAAUUGUUGAUGAGGUCUUGGAGCCUCCCUUCUGCUCCCAGAAGCUUUUGUUGCUCAUGUCUCCAGCCACAAUAUCCUUGCAGGACAGAGUCUUGGCUGCAGACUGAGCCUGUACCUCACCCGUCUCCCACCGACUCUUGGUACUGGCCACGGCCAUGCUGGGCAGCUCUAUGGAGGCCUGGCGGGCUAGCUUGGGUGUCCUGCCAGUGGUACUUUCACAGCUGGGGAGUGGAGCCUGGGCCUGAGGUCUCCUGUGCGACUCUCCGCACCUGCGCCGGUGCCAUGCGCCUCUCCGCGCCUUUUCUCACCAUGGGGCAGCAUUUCGGGGCCUCUUGAGGGACCCCUAGAUGCUUCUACUCAAAGCCCCCAAAGCCAAGGAGCCUCCACUCCUCCGUCUGCAGCCCCCCCUCCCGGUUCUCGCUACGCAGGGUUCAGUGGCCUUGGGGCUGACGGAGGAGGUUGCGUCUGCCAAGGCCCCUACCAGCGCCUCCCUGGCUCAUCCAGCCCACCUCCCUCCCACGCUGGCUCAAGCAAAGUGCUCUGGUCACCAGGAGCCCUUCCUGACCAGCCCCGGCCCCUUCUUGGCCUUCACCCCACCUGGCCUCCCCUGGAGGCCUAGCCUGGGUGCCGGGCCUGCUGGGUCCAGAGCCCACCCCGCCCUGAACAACCCCGAGCCCAUAUUUUCAAAUAUAAUCAGAUCAUAUACCUUCCUUGCUUAAAAAGGGCGAAACUCCAUCUUAAAAAAAAAAAGCCUCAACAUCUCUCUAUUAAAUAUAGGAUCUAAAGUCAAUCCCAUGGAACAAAUAAUCUUGAAAGGUUUCUAGACUGUCUUUUCGACUCACUUUGCUCUGUUUCAAAAAGGUUCACCAAGUCCCAAGAAAACAGAACAGCUUUCUGCUCAUUGAACCCAGAGAACCCAGUUUUACACUGAAGAUUUUAUUUAUUCUUCUCUCUGAUUGGAAGAAAGCUACUUUCUUUUACUCUUCAAAUAACAAGAUAGUUUUUCAUCCUUCACGUUAGGGCGUCUUUAACCAACUCCAAAUUUCUUUCUGUCUUUCAAACCUUACAGCUUUCAUAACACUUGAAACCAUUUUACUAACCUGCUCUUUAAAAUAGAGACAAUCACUGUUUUCUUUAUUUCUGGGUCUUUAAUAUCUAAAAGAGAUAUAGUAGAUAUGAUAAUAUGGUAGGGGACAAUGUAUAUGUAAUGAGUAUAUGAGUGAAAGAUAUUGUGCUUUAUUAUGAUAUAAGGAAUGGAUAGAUUUUACUAUAUUUUAAGCACAAAAAUGGGUCAGAUUUGGAAUUGUAUUCAACACUGAGGCAACAAUGUAGAAGAUGGCUUUUUAAUACCUAAUAUUCUGAUUUAAUUCACUGUCCGAAUGAAAAAUACCCUUAGAAGGUUUGACUAAAUACGUAAUUUCUUGACCAA